GCACACGCUGCGCGCUCUCACGCGCAUACACACGCCCUCCCUGCCGCGCUCGCCGCCGCGGCCACCAUCGCGGAGCCGAGCCCUGCGGAGCGGGAACCGAGGCCGGAGCGGGGACCGGAGGCAGCCGAGCCGGGGGAUGCCGGCCCGGAGCGGAGCCGCGCGCGGACGGCGCGCCCGGGACGCCUCCGGCACCCACAGGCCCUGAGGCUCCAGUGCCCACAGGCAGAGAGGGCGACUGAGUCCAGCCCAGGCUGAGCCCUGCCCAGCUGUACUCCCCAGACACCCACCCAACCCGAGGUGUCCCACCGAGGAGGCCCUGAUCUUGAGCCCGGAGCCCUGAGCCCUGAGACGAUGCUUGACUGACCGUGAGACACCAGAGCCGUACCAGCCUCAAACACCUGAUGUGCACAGCGUGCCAGUGGAGAGGAGCCCAGCCCCCUUCAGAGCAGCCAGGGACACCUUCCUGGAGGAAGUGGUCCCAGCACUUGUCCUGAGAUGAAUGGAGAGGAGGGUGGCCCUGGGCACCUGUUGGGGACAGGCAGAAAGGAUAUUUGGAGAAUACUAAGGCCAAGGUGGAGGGAUCUUAUGACCAUGACCUGGCUACCUUGAGUCUGUGGGGCUACACAGCCUUCAGCCUGCAUCUCCAGGGCUCUGACUCUAUCCAGCUCCUGGACCAGCUCCCAAGUCUACUCCUGACCCCAGCCUGGGCCAAGGGGACUUCUCAAGCUUUGGGACCCAGCAGGACACAGCAGCAGUCAGGUGCAUGCUGGGACCGCGACGGACAGGCUGCCGCACCCCAGGCCCCCAGAGGCCAGUCUGUUUGCCUCCCAACGCCAUCUGACCCAGGUGAGCAAGAGGAUGCUGGCGGGGGGCGUGAGGAGCAUGCCCAGCCCCCUCCUGGCCUGCUGGCAGCCCAUCCUCCUGCUGGUGCUGGGCUCAGUGCUGUCAGGCUCGGCCACGGGCUGCCCGCCCCGCUGCGAGUGCUCCGCCCAGGACCGCGCUGUGCUGUGCCACCGCAAGCGCUUUGUGGCAGUCCCCGAGGGCAUCCCCACCGAGACGCGCCUGCUGGACCUAGGCAAGAACCGCAUCAAAACGCUCAACCAGGACGAGUUCGCCAGCUUCCCGCACCUGGAGGAGCUGGAGCUCAACGAGAACAUCGUGAGCGCCGUGGAGCCCGGCGCCUUCAACAACCUCUUCAACCUCCGGACGCUGGGUCUCCGCAGCAACCGCCUGAAGCUCAUCCCGCUAGGCGUCUUCACUGGCCUCAGCAACCUGACCAAGCUGGACAUCAGCGAGAACAAGAUCGUUAUCCUACUGGACUACAUGUUUCAGGACCUGUACAACCUCAAGUCACUGGAGGUUGGCGACAAUGACCUCGUCUACAUCUCUCACCGCGCCUUCAGCGGCCUCAACAGCCUGGAGCAGCUGACGCUGGAGAAAUGCAACCUGACCUCCAUCCCCACCGAGGCGCUGUCCCACCUGCACGGCCUCAUCGUCCUGAGGCUCCGGCACCUCAACAUCAAUGCCAUCCGGGACUACUCCUUCAAGAGGCUGUACCGACUCAAGGUCUUGGAGAUCUCCCACUGGCCCUACUUGGACACCAUGACACCCAACUGCCUCUACGGCCUCAACCUGACGUCCCUGUCCAUCACACACUGCAAUCUGACCGCUGUGCCCUACCUGGCCGUCCGCCACCUAGUCUAUCUCCGCUUCCUCAACCUCUCCUACAACCCCAUCAGCACCAUUGAGGGCUCCAUGUUGCAUGAGCUGCUCCGGCUGCAGGAGAUCCAGCUGGUGGGCGGGCAGCUGGCCGUGGUGGAGCCCUAUGCCUUCCGCGGCCUCAACUACCUGCGCGUGCUCAAUGUCUCUGGCAACCAGCUGACCACACUGGAGGAAUCAGUCUUCCACUCGGUGGGCAACCUGGAGACACUCAUCCUGGACUCCAACCCGCUGGCCUGCGACUGUCGGCUCCUGUGGGUGUUCCGGCGCCGCUGGCGGCUCAACUUCAACCGGCAGCAGCCCACGUGCGCCACGCCCGAGUUUGUCCAGGGCAAGGAGUUCAAGGACUUCCCUGAUGUGCUACUGCCCAACUACUUCACCUGCCGCCGCGCCCGCAUCCGGGACCGCAAGGCCCAGCAGGUGUUUGUGGACGAGGGCCACACGGUGCAGUUUGUGUGCCGGGCCGAUGGCGACCCGCCGCCCGCCAUCCUCUGGCUCUCACCCCGAAAGCACCUGGUCUCAGCCAAGAGCAAUGGGCGGCUCACAGUCUUCCCUGAUGGCACGCUGGAGGUGCGCUACGCCCAGGUACAGGACAACGGCACGUACCUGUGCAUCGCGGCCAACGCGGGCGGCAACGACUCCAUGCCCGCCCACCUGCAUGUGCGCAGCUACUCGCCCGACUGGCCCCAUCAGCCCAACAAGACCUUCGCUUUCAUCUCCAACCAGCCGGGCGAGGGAGAGGCCAACAGCACCCGCGCCACUGUGCCUUUCCCCUUCGACAUCAAGACCCUCAUCAUCGCCACCACCAUGGGCUUCAUCUCUUUCCUGGGCGUCGUCCUCUUCUGCCUGGUGCUGCUGUUUCUCUGGAGCCGGGGCAAGGGCAACACAAAGCACAACAUCGAGAUCGAGUAUGUGCCCCGAAAGUCGGACGCAGGCAUCAGCUCCGCCGACGCGCCCCGCAAGUUCAACAUGAAGAUGAUAUGAGGCCGGGGCGGGGGGCAGGGACCCCCGGGCGGCCGGGCAGGGGAAGGGGCCUGGCCGCCACCUGCUCACUCUCCAGUCCUUCCCACCUCCUCCCUACCCUUCUACACACGUUCUCUUUCUCCCUCCCGCCUCCGUCCCCUGCUGCCCCCCGCCAGCCCUCACCACCUGCCCUCCUUCUACCAGGACCUCAGAAGCCCAGACCUGGGGACCCCACCUACACAGGGGCAUUGACAGACUGGAGUUGAAAGCCGACGAACCGACACGCGGCAGAGUCAAUAAUUCAAUAAAAAAGUUACGAACUUUCUCUGUAACUUGGGUUUCAAUAAUUAUGGAUUUUUAUGAAAACUUGAAAUAAUAAAAAGAGAAAAAAACUAUUUCCUAUAGCUAGUCGGAAUGCAAACUUUUGACGUCCUGAUUGCUCCAGGGCCCUCUUCCAACUCAGUUUCUUGUUUUUCUCUUCCUCCUCCUCCUCUUCUUCCUCCUUUCUCUUCUCUUCCCCAGUGGGGAGGGAUCACUCAGGAAAACAGGAAAGGAGGUUCCAGCCCCACCCACCUGCCCACCCCGCCCCAGGCACCAUCAGGAGCAGGCUAGGGGGCAGGCCUGGGCCCAGCUCCGGGCUGGCUUUUUGCAGGGCGCAGGUGGAGGGGACAGGUCUGCCGAUGGGGGUGGGAGCCUGUCUGCUGGGCUGCCAGGCGGCACCACUGCAAGGGGUGGGAGCCUGGCUUGGGUGUGGCUGAGACUCUGGACAGAGGCUGGGGUCCUCCUGGGGGACAGCACAGUCAGUGGAGAGAGCCAGGGGCUGGAGGUGGGGCCCACCCCAGCCUCUGGUCCCAGCUCUGCUGCUCACUUGCUGUGUGGCCUCAAGCAGGUCACUGGCCUCUCUGGGCCUCAGUCUCCACAUCUGUACAAAUGGGAACAUUACCCCCUGCCCUGCCUACCUCACAGGGCUGUUGUGAGGAAUUGAUGAGAUGAUGUAUGUGAAACACUUUGUAACCUGUAAAGCGCUGUGCACACGUG